GCUUGCAGGACCCUGACCCCAAGAUGGCGGCGCCCAGCGAAGUGGCCGCGAUAGCCCCUGGCGAAGGCGAUGGCGGAGGCGGCGGCUUUGGCUCCUGGCUGGACGGACGGUUGGAGGCACUGGGAGUGGACCGAGCCGUUUAUGGAGCCUACAUCUUGGGUAUCCUGCAGGAGGAGGAGGAAGAAGAGAAGCUGGACGCUCUGCAGGGGAUCCUCUCUGCUUUCCUGGAAGAAGAUUCCCUCCUUAAUAUCUGCAAGGAGAUUGUGGAACGAUGGUCAGAAACUCAGAAUGUUGUCACCAAAGUGAAAAAAGAAGAUGAAGUACAGGCCAUUGCCACCCUAAUUGAGAAGCAGGCACAAAUCGUAGUAAAGCCAAGGAUGGUGUCAGAAGAGGAGAAGCAGAGAAAAGCUGCCCUCCUGGCCCAGUAUGCUGAUGUGACAGAUGAAGAGGAUGAAGCAGAUGAGAAGGAUGAUUCAGGUGCUACCACAAUGAACAUUGGUUCUGACAAACUUCUGUUCCGAAACACCAAUGUGGAAGAUGUCCUUAAUGCCCGAAAACUGGAGCGAGACUCACUUCGGGAUGAAUCCCAAAGGAAGAAGGAACAGGACAAGCUGCAGAGGGAGAGAGACAAACUAGCCAAGCAGGAGCGCAAGGAAAAGGAAAAAAAAAGGACACAGAGAGGGGAGCGAAAGCGAUAACCUUGGCCUACUCUAUUCUUUCCCCCCAUGAACUUAUCAAAGGGAGAACUGGUUGUGUAUUUAAGAGAAAUGAGAGUGCAUUGCAAAGUAGUUUCCCAAGGCAUUUCCCCUAUUGUUUACAUGGUCAAAAGGAAAAUCAAAAUCACUUCUAAUUACAAAAUGUGCUGUUUUGGUGGGGUGGGCAAUCAGAUUAUUAUAGUUGAUGACUGUACCAAAGAUCUGGAAUGGGGGCCACCUUUAUAUUUUAAUACUCAAGUCCUGUGCUCCUUUUGGCCACUUUAAAAAGUCUUCCCUCACCUUGGAUAAAUAGGAUUCAGAAAGCUAACAGUUUUCAUUCUGAAGGAGCAGAAACAUAAUCAAUCCCUCCCUGAGAUAAAAUGUGGGCAUGCACAUUGCUUUGGAGUCAGUAUUCAGCUGUAAGUGUAGUAUUGUUUUAUGGCUGAAAUAGAAAGCUAAUGAAGAGGCCUACCUGGAUCCAGAUUUUAUGUUAACAUGGCAGCAAAACUAGGAAAAUGGGAAGAAAUUACUUGCGGGGUGUUCUAGAUCUGAUUUUUUUUUUUUUUUUGAAAGUUUCAGCCUGUGGGAGGAAAAGAGGUAUCUUUUAAAAUAGAGAUAGUUACAUAUUUUCCUCAUCUAGGCUGUGUCACUAUUGGGUGCAAGGAUAUCAUUGUUGGCUAGAUUCAUUUUGUAUAAUCAUGUAUCCUCUUGUGUGCUGGUAGAGAUUUUAAUCCUGAUUUUUCCAUAAAACAUGAGUAUUAAGAAAUAAUUCCUGGUUUGGAGAAACUGGAGAAAUCACCCUUUUAAGGAAGAAACACUGGAAAUUUCUGCUAACACCAAGAUAUUUAAGAGUGUACAUAGUAGGUGCUCAACAAAUUUAUUGAAUGAAUGAGUGAAUGGAAAAACUGGGAGAGUCAAAAGUGAGCAGAAGCUCUCCAUUUCUACUUCUGUCACAAACCACAUUAAAUUGUAAAUAAGGCCCUUCUCCACUUGACUUCAGGCAGCAGAUUGUCUAGAAGCCUAAGGACAGCAAUUUCUCUGACAAGACAAAGUAGAUAUUUUAUACCAGGGGUUGGCAAACUACUGCCCACGGGCCGAAUUUGGCCCAGUCUGUUUUUGUAUGGUGCAAACUAAAAAUGAUUUUUACAUUUUUAAAGAGUUAUAAAAGAAAAAAAUAUGUGGUCUGUGAAAUCUAAAAUAUUUACUACCUGGCCUGUUGGAGGAAAGGUUUGCCAAUCUCUGUUUUAUACCAUUAACUAUGAGAUUAACAAAAACUUUUACCUUUGUGCAGAAGGUUAAAAAAAAAAAAACAUGGUUAAGGAAAAGGAGACAUGUUACCUCUUCAUACACUCCUAUAACUGUGGCAUUGCAAAAAAUAAAAAUAACCACCUUUAAAAAAAUAAAUCUUAUUUAAAUUGC